AGCAGCAGCAGCAGCAGCAGCAGCAGCAGCUGCGAGUGCGCGCGUGUGGGUGUGAGGGUGAGUGCGCUGGCGCCGGCUGCAGCGCCCUGCCCAGCUCCCCGCCAGCUUCCCUACCCCCGCCUGCCGGAGCCGCCCUCCCGUGGGACCAGCACCCUCAUUCCGGCCAGGCAAGCCUGAAUCCUGUCCCUGCCAUCUCGCCACUGCAGCUCGGGUCCAGAAAGGCACCAUUUUGUCGCGGCUGCCCGCUCUCCCAGGGGGAGGAGGGAUCUUUUUUGCAUUUUGGAGCGGCUGCCAAGGAGGGGAACCUGUUGGGCAUCUCCCCAGACCCGCUUGUGAGCGCCUCCGGGGCGGGCGGGCGGGACCAGACCCCUCGGGGCACGGCGUAUCUUGGCACCCGGAGGCAGCGGAGGCAGGCGCAGCAUCCUCGCUGGGAACUGGAGCUGGAGUGAGCGCACCGCGCGGGAGGAGCCGCCGCAGCCUCGCAGAACCCGAGUGGAGGAGGUGACAGCUCCAUUGCCGGGUUUUUAUUUUUUUUCUCUCCGCCUCCCCGUCUCCUCCUCAGGCUCGGACCAUGGUGCAGUCCCACUGGCUCCCCUGCCCCCCUCUCCUGUGAGACUGGCUGCGGGGAGGGAUCAUGGAUACUUGUCUGCCGGCUUCUGGUUCCCACGCAAGUAAGCCUGCUGUCAAUGGAGGAGGACAUUGAUACCCGCAAAAUCAACAACAGUUUCCUGCGCGACCACAGCUAUGCGACCGAAGGAGCCAAGGGAGAACCCAAGACAGAGAAUAGUGGCCCAAUAAUGAAGCAUGAAUUAUCCAGAUGAAAACACCUAUGGAAAUAAAGCUGACAUUAUCUCUACGGUAGAAUUCAACCACACGGGAGAAUUACUAGCGACAGGGGACAAGGGGGGUCGGGUUGUAAUAUUUCAACGAGAGCAGGAGAGUAAAAAUCAGGUUCAUCGUAGGGGUGAAUACAAUGUUUACAGCACAUUCCAGAGCCAUGAACCCGAGUUCGAUUACCUGAAGAGUUUAGAAAUAGAAGAAAAAAUCAAUAAAAUAAGAUGGCUCCCCCAGCAGAAUGCAGCUUACUUUCUUCUGUCUACUAAUGAUAAAACUGUGAAGCUGUGGAAAGUCAGCGAGCGUGAUAAGAGGCCAGAAGGCUACAAUCUGAAAGAUGAGGAGGGCCGGCUCCGGGAUCCUGCCACCAUCACAACCCUGCGGGUGCCUGUCCUGAGACCCAUGGACCUGAUGGUGGAGGCCACCCCACGAAGAGUAUUUGCCAACGCACACACAUAUCACAUCAACUCCAUAUCUGUCAACAGCGACUAUGAAACCUACAUGUCCGCUGAUGACCUGAGGAUUAACCUAUGGAACUUUGAAAUAACCAAUCAAAGUUUUAAUAUUGUGGACAUUAAGCCAGCCAACAUGGAGGAGCUCACGGAGGUGAUCACAGCAGCCGAGUUCCACCCCCAUCAUUGCAACACCUUCGUGUACAGCAGCAGCAAAGGGACAAUCCGGCUGUGUGACAUGCGGGCAUCUGCCCUGUGUGACAGGCACACCAAAUUUUUUGAAGAGCCGGAAGAUCCAAGCAACAGAUCAUUUUUCUCUGAAAUUAUCUCUUCGAUUUCGGAUGUGAAGUUCAGCCACAGUGGGAGGUAUAUCAUGACCAGGGACUACUUGACCGUCAAAGUCUGGGAUCUCAACAUGGAAAACCGCCCCAUCGAGACUUACCAGGUUCAUGACUACCUCCGCAGCAAGCUGUGUUCCCUCUAUGAAAAUGACUGCAUUUUUGAUAAAUUUGAGUGUGUGUGGAAUGGGUCAGACAGUGUCAUCAUGACAGGCUCCUACAACAACUUCUUCAGGAUGUUCGACAGAAACACCAAGCGUGAUGUGACCCUUGAGGCUUCGAGGGAAAACAGCAAGCCCCGGGCUAUCCUCAAACCCCGAAAAGUGUGUGUGGGGGGCAAGCGGAGAAAAGACGAGAUCAGUGUCGACAGUCUGGACUUUAGCAAAAAGAUCUUGCAUACAGCUUGGCAUCCUUCAGAAAAUAUUAUAGCAGUGGCGGCUACAAAUAACCUAUAUAUAUUCCAGGACAAGGUUAACUAGGUGGACAAGUUAUUACUUAAUAAUCUCACAUACUGAAUACUAGUCAAACAAGUUUUUAAAUGUUUCUUUGGGUCUUCAUUUGAUGCAUUGACUUUAAUUUCCCUAUACAGGAAAUGAUUGGAAUAGAAUUAAAAGGAGUCCAACAUUCCCAGCUCCCCAGUUCUAAGAAACUUUUGUCAAACCCAAUAGGUUUGGGACACUUCUGUUUAGAAUUGAAAGCUGCCAGCUAACAGUAAUUCUUCCAUAGUUGACUUGAACUUCUGAUGCUUUUAUUGCCCAGUUUUCUCUGGUGGGUCCAGUGUUUUGUUCCUAGGUGUCUGCUGCGAUAAAAUGAGGUUGUCUGUAGUAUUUAAGGAGAAAAGAGAUAAGUUUUUUUUAAUUAAGCAAUUCCAUUUGAUUGAAAAAAAUCAACAAAAAAUAAACACCGUUUACUCUUAGACAAAUUCUUCUUGUUUUGUGAAAAACCAGAACUAGUCAGUAUCUCCUGCCCCUCCACCAUUUUUUUUUCCAUUUUCCAUUUUCCUUUGAACAAUUUCAUUUAAGCCAGAGAUUUAUUGCAUGAAGCUGAGAAGAGGAUGCAGAAUGACAAGGAAAGGGCACAUCAACCCUGCUAUGCUCUUUUUUUGUAAGCUCCAUAGAAACAGCCUGAGAAUUUGGCUAGGGAACUUGAAUGCUUCAGGGGACAGAAAGAGAGCACUUUCGACACAGUGCUUCCCAGAGUGAGCUUGGCAGGGCCAGGCGGGGCCAAAUUCCAUCUGCUGCCUUGUUACUCUUGCUUUUUGUGCUCUUAAAUGGCUCCAUAUAAUCUUCUACUUACAUGUUCCUUGGCUUUUUUCUCUUCAACCUUUUCCAGCUUAUUUAUUCCAUUGACUUCUAAAGGCCGAGUCCUGGGUGCUUAUUAUCUGGUGUUCUAAAUGAAGCAGUAAGUUGGAAGCAGUGCCACCACCCCUGAGUCCCUGAGAAAGGCUGGUCUGUUCUUUUUGGGUGUUUCUCCUAAGCAGCACCCUCCCCUCCUCCUGGUUUUGGUAACCAAAAGUAACAAUCCAUCAACCUCCAUUGUACCUAGAACAAAAAUAGCCAAUAAAAACGCUGAGUUGUGAAGUCCAAUCAGGCACUUCUAACUCACCCCAAGCUCGCCAUCUGGAAAAACAGACCAGAAGGCUCUCUUCUACAGAAAUGAACUGUGGGGAAAUCAAGCAGCUGUGACAUGAAGUGAAUGAAGUCCACUUGAAGCUGUGGAAGAUGGUUCAUCCUUUUCCCCAGUUGAGGAUCCAGAUUUAUAACUUCUAGAAAGCCAUUUCCAGAAGGUUCUAUGUGGCACACCCCUAGGAAAGGCACUAAAUGCAUGCAAAGGAUUUAUAAACUUAGGAAAGUAGAUGGGUGGAGUCCAGAAAACUGGUUCUGGGUUAAUAUCUCUACAUCUGUCUUGAUGACUCAUUUCUCCUAACUCCCAUUUAGUGCAGGGUAAAUGGUUUGAGAUGAGAGUUUUUCAAUGAAAGGGAAAUUUUCUUUCAGUUUACAGAUGUAUUAGAAGUCCUGACUUUCAAGUGUAAUUUGCUUUGGAGGAGGAAAAAAUAGUGAAAGAAUCAUUUUAUCUCAAUUCUAAGCUACUAUCCAUUUACUAAUAGCUUUUUGGCAAGGAAAUAACUGUCACCUUAGGUAAAAACAGUCUUGUUAGAUGCAGCCCAAUUUCAGGAACAUUAAAAUGUAAAAAAGUACGUCUCAGAAUUGAGGGAGCAUGGGAACAAAGACGAGACUUUCUCAGUAUUUCUCAUUUUUCCUGCAAGGAAAGCCUCGCCUUAGGCAUCUCAAGUAAAGUGGCUAAGGUGUAAACUCUCUGGGCAAGAUUUCUGUCCUGACUGGGACAGUGUUCUUGGAGGAGACAUGAGAGAGUCAGAAACUUCUGCCAGUCAUAGAGAGUGAUGAUUUUGCAGAAGGCCACUGGGUUAUUGGCCUACAUUUACCACCGACUUCCUUUAUGGCCUUUUCUCCACUUCUCCGGACUCAGCUCCUCUGUCUGUACCACGUCGGGGGUUGGGACCAAUCAUUGUAUCUCAAACUUAAGAAUCAACUCACAUUUGUACUAUUACUCAUGUAACAUUUUUUUAAGUCACCUUUUCUUAAAAGCAAGACUUAGCCUCCUCCAAAGAAAUAAUAUGCAUGAAAUUUCAACUCUGAUAUGCUAGGUUUUUCCCUAACAUUAAUCACAUAAUUAUCAAUGUAACAAACAUGCACCCACAUACCACCUGAAAUCAUUUUGUGAACCACCAGGAGCAUGUGUAUCAAACUUUGGGACCCUGAGUAACUGAUAUGACAGAAGAUUUAUGCCCUUAGGGGCAUCAAAGAUGGUGGUUCUUCACAUAUUAGAGUCAGCAGGGCUGCCCAUAACACACACAGGAAUAAUUUUUGUCAUGGUUUAAGGAGUUCAUAGGCCCCUUUGCAGUUUAUCUGCGAACUCCAAAUAAAAGCCCCUACACUAGUCCAACACCCUUAGCAUAUAGAUGUACAAACUGGGAUCCAGAGUAGGAUGAGUUUGCCAGAGAAGAAAGAGCAGAGGGCAGCCAUCCUCUCCUCCAUCCCCUGCAAAGGAUGCAUUAGAGCAAACACCCAAGACUCCUGGACGGGAACAGGAGGGGAAAGCCCUAGAGAUUAGGCCUCAGGGAGCAAUAACCACCACGAUGUUUCACAAAUUAACUGUUCUUUACCAGGUACUGAACUAGGUAUUUUACAUGUGUGAUCUUUCAGCCCCAGUACUGGCAAUAUUUCUUAGUUAGUGGCACAUAGAAGUCAGUCUGUUUUCCUGCUGACACUAAAAACUACUUGAAGGCUGAUUUGCUACCUUGCAACAGUUGGUUCGAUUCUAAGGGCCCUAUACUACUUUACCCCACAAGGCCUGCUGCUUGGUAAGAGCCAUCAGAUUACAACUGGAGGGUGUCAGUUGAAUGAAGGAAAAUGGAAGCCACGCCAUCCCUGGCUUUUACAAAAACCAUCCUUGCGCAACAUUCAGUUCCUGACGUUAAAAACAAGUAAUGCAAAAAGCUGAACUUUGGUAGACAUUCGUACUCUUCUGUCAGGAGGAGGAAGAUUAGUUAGAAAAAACAAAAAAGGAAGAUACUAGCCAGCAUCAAGAAGUGGGAUAUAUAAAGGCAGAUGGGCAGUGGGAAUCAAGUUGCUUCUUAACUCCUUCAAGUUUGGCUCCUGCCUUUACUCUUCCAUUGAAAAAAAAGCACCUUUAAACCUCUCAUUGAUCUUGUAAUUAAUUCAACCAAAUCAACUUCUAUUAGGCAACCAGCAUAUAUAAGAUGGAACAAUUGCAAGGUGGAAUAAAGAUGAAGCUAAAAUUCUGCUAGCUCAGUGGCCCAAUGAAAUAAGUCAGCUAUCUCCACUAAACUUCCUUUGAAUAUUCUAGGGUCCAUUAUAAUAAAAGGUACACACUCAAAUGCCCAAUUUCUAAGGACUUGAAAAGCCAUAAUUUCCCUCCCUUCAAGCCUACAGAGCAACUGCCUAAAGCUUCCCUCCCCAGACAACCCCAGGCCUCAUUUCUUUUUCAGUCCCUUUGCUAGCUGCCUGCAGGGCUCAAGAAAGCCCUGGUAGGCCUCAUAAUGAGGAUUUAGGGAUGACACUAUAGUCCACAGCCUGAAUGGUGGAACCCUUACUAAUUUUCCCUCUUCCGUGAUGAAUGUGUGGAUGAAGCCGGUGUGUUUUUAAUAAUGCCACCCCACUUCCAAAACAAAUCCCCUGACACAGUCUUUGGACAUACCACCCUGAAUGCACCCGAUCUCAUCUGAUCUUGGAAGUGAAAUGGAGUCAGGCCUGGUUAGUCUUUGGAUGGGGGAAGUCUAGACACACCACUGAGAAACAUUCACACUGCAACCUGAUUCACUGUGCAUCCAACAUGCCUUCAUCCACCUCUUCCCCCUGAACUUCUAAGUCAACUCUCAGGGACUGCUUUCCAAGGGAGCAACCAACCUGGUCAGUGGAAAAAGGAUGAGACUGGGAGACAGGAAACGUGGGUCCUGCUCCUGGUAACCAUGGAACUUAAGCUACCCACUCAGUCCCUAUGUCAGUGUCAUCACCUGUAAAAUGGCCAGAAAGACAUCUAUCCUAGCUCAGAGAAUUGUUAUUGGGAGAACAAGAAAUCCAUUUACUUACAACUAUUUUGAUAGGUUUAAAGCACCAUAAACUAAUAAUAGCAACAACAGUGAUGGGUAAUAUACUAUUGCUUUCCAUGCCUCAUCUCAUUAUCUCCUCUCCCAGACCCCAUGGUGGCAUUAGUAUUUCCAUUUUGCAAAUGAGAAAAUAGACUCAAGUUGUCAACCUAGCCAAGGGCACAAAGCCCGAGAGAGAUGGAACCAGGACUCCAACUCAAGGUAUCUGACUCUAAAGCCAGAGCUGUUAAAAUACAGCUCUAACAUACAAUAGUUGCUAACAUUUAUUGAGCACUUAUUAUAAGCCAGGCUUUGUUCUACAAAUUUCACAUGUAUUGACUUAUUUACCCCUAAAACUCCAGAUGCAGAUACUAUUGUUGUUCUCAUUUUAUAGAUACAGAAACAGAUGAAUGACAACCAAAUUUACACAGUUCACAAGUGACAAAGCCAGGCAGUUUUAGUUAAAGUUCUUAUCCACUAUCCCCAUCAUACAUUAUGUGUGUGUGUGUGUGUGUGUGUGUGUGUGUGUGUGUGUGUGUAUGCAUGUAGAUGGAAGUUACUGAUCAGAAAACAAGCCCCAGUAAUGACCCAUAAGCUCAAUGAAUUAAAGAUUCAUUGGUUGCCUGGGAUGUGUCAGGCAGCCAGGUUCUAGACAAGGGGCUGGAGUUACUAAGAUAUUUAAACCACUGGCCCCUGCCCUCCAAGAGAUGACACUCACAUAGGAGAAAGUGCAUAUUUGCAUACUGUAAACAUUUUUACAAUGAGAUAUCUAUGAAGGGCAGAAGUCAUACAGAGGAAGAAAUAGUUAAUCAAUGAGUGAUAAGAAAAGGUUCUCAGAAUGUGUCAUCUAAGCAGAAUUUUAACUAAAUUUGCUCAACAAAGCAUGAUACAGCGUUUCCAAUAGGUAGACCAACAUAUACCAGAAUAUGAAGCAAAAUCCAUAUGGCAUGGAAACAGAAAGCCAAUGUUUCUCUCCUUCCAUUAGAAACACAUUUUCGACAUACUAGAACUAGCCUACCCCUUUUUCCUUUUGUUCAUCCAAUAACAAAUAUUUAUUAAACCUUAUUUUAAGCACUGUAUUUAAGUGUAAAGUAGACGGAAAGAAUAAAAGGAAACCAAUAUUUCCUGAGUAGUUAUUGCAAUGACAGGCAUUGGGAGAGGCACUGUUUUAAAUCAUUGUUAAUCACCUGAUAGGUAGAUGUAUUAUUCCAUUUUUAUAGCGAGAAACAGACUCAAAAGGGUUAGAUGACGUAGCAGGAAGUUUUAUCUAGAUCUAUCCUGUUCCAGAUCCUAUACUUCUUCCAUCACAGUUAUUGGUAAUGCAGAGUUACCUUGGCUUGAUUAUUUUCCCUAGCGUGGAUACUCACAAACACGCCAUUUCUCUGUGACUAAAUAUUGCCUGACAGCUGACCAAGAAUACAAAUUUGGUCUGUCAUCAAAGCAGAGAGUGAAGUCAAGUGGCUCACAGGUCUCCAACUUCUGACUUUGACCUUAUUAUGACUGAUUAACUGUCCCCCAAUUUAGAUAUUCCAUGCCCCAUUGGUUAAACUGCUGGUGGCAGAACCAUCAUGAUCUGCCAUCUCCGCUGAUCCCUGCCUCAGCUGCAAUCAAAGCAAUGAUCACUGUCAGGCCAGAAGAAGGGGCUUAGCCACUGCCAAGACAGAUCCCAGUCCACUCCCAGCCUUCCCGCCCCUGCUGCUCAUUCCCCAAAAAGUCAACCUGGGUUUUCCUGGGUGAACAGUGCCCACUGAACAGCUCCUGCUUGCCCAUCUCAAGCCCUCUCAGUUGCCACUCCAAUCAUUUUGGCUGCUGUAUUUGGUUUGAGAAAGAGUGGAGAGGACACUUCUUCAUAACUCAUAUUUGACAGAAACCCAGAAAUUGUAGGAACAAGCCAUGAUUGCUGUGAUUCUUGCUCUGGUUGGCUAGGGAUGCCCUCCCUUCCAGCCAGAGUAAUACAUACUUGUGGGAGUCAUGGAAGACUGAGGAAGCUGGAGUAGAAGGGAACAGGGGCUUUCCUCAGUGGUAAAAGGAAAAGCAACAUUUUGGAACUCUAAACAGUUGCUCAGUUGGGCGAAUUUCAUGCAUUCAUUCAUUCAUUUACUAAAUGGUUAAUGAUUGUUCAUGUACUGCCUGCCAAGCCCAUGCCAGGGUGGUCUGUGGAAGCAGCAGUGACAGCUCCAUCUUCACACAGCUCACAGAUAGCGGGAGGUGCAGACAAACUCACAGGCAAUGGUGGCAGUGGAAUGUCAAGAGCCCAGGAUACCGAGCCUGCCAGCCUGCCUGCCUGGGUUAAAAUCUGAGCUCCACCAUGUAAAAGCUGAGCAACCUAGAAAAAUGACAACCUCUCUGUGCCUCGAUUUUCUCAUUAUGAGAUAAGGAUAAAAACGACAUCUAUCUCAUAAAAUUGCUGUGAAGAUUGCAUGAUUUAAUAUGCACAAAGCUCUUAGAAGGAUGCCUGGCCCACAAAUAUGCAUUCAGUGCACAUUUCUUGCUACAGUUCUGCUAAUCCUAUAAAACAUAUGCACUAUGAUGGAUGUGUCUGGGUGCCAGGAGGACACAAAGGAGCACUAACUCAUCCAGACCAGAAGCUUCCCAGAGGAGGUGAUUCCCAAGGUGAAAUCCGAAAGAUAAAGGGAGUGAGUUAUCCAGGAGAAGAGAAAGGAAAAGCAUAUUCCAGACAUCAGGAUAGGACAGUGGAGGCAAAACAGCAUAUGCUAUAUAUAUAUGGAAUUCACAACACUCUGGUAUGACUGAUUAGUAAAAAGUAGGAAGGCAGACCAAGAGAAAUAAGGAGACAUGGUAAGGUGAGUGGGCAAUAAUGCAUGAUCUGAAAAAUAAUAAUGCAUGGACUUAGUGUGGUUCACAUAUCAGGAGCUUCUCCAAUAGCCAGGCUAUGAGGCACUAAAAUGAGGAAAUAUGGUUUCCAAACUUCGCAAAUACUUAUAGUCCAGCCACAGGGGAUAUACUGAUAAACUCAGCUCAAAUGUCACCUCCUCAGAGAUGCUUUCUCAACCACCCUUAGUUCCAUGAGGACUGCAUCAUUGUUUAGGCCACUCCUGUAUCCCCAGAGCACAGAACAUUGUCUGGCUCAUAGUAGGUGCUCAAAAGUUUUGUUGAAUGAAUGAACAAAUAAACGUGUAAGGAAGUCAGGCACAGCACUUGCCCACAGGAAGCUUAUAAGAUGAGCGGCAUGCCAUUGGGAGUUUGAAUGAUAUAUGGAGAUCCAAACAGGGCAUCAGAGGACUGCUCAGAGGAGUCAGGGAAUUAAGAAAAAAUUGGGAGCCAGUGAGCCAAGAUGUGUUAAAAGCAAGUGAUCAAGCUUAGAUUGCAGUGUUAGUUAAUAGAGCAUAUGUGUCCCUGCCUGAUGCAUUACCUUCCCUGCAGUAGUUAGCCUUCUGGGACCCUGAAAAGCAUGCAGAAAGGUUGACAGCUUACAAUCAAUACCAUGUUCACUGAUGCAGGAAGCAACAUUAUCACAUCCAAGAUAUUGCCCCCACACCCAGGCUGCAGCACUAAAUAUUCCCCAUAACAAGGCAAAGGGAAGUGACAAGAGCUAUUAUUCUCAACCCUCCCACUUGGAAACAAGAGGUGAGACAAACCUUCCCCUAGAUGUUCUUAGGGAAAGGCAAGACCCCCAAAGAAAUCUUUCAGAGCUGAGCACAUGCCUAAUACAGCAAGACAGGGAUGGGAGAAGAUUGGCAUUUUCAUUUGCCUGGGUGUCCACAAUAUUGCAGGGGAAGCUCUGUGGGCAGCUGGGAAAUACAACAAUAAAUUGGAGGGGGAUGAACAAUAGGGUCAGUGGGGCUGUGUGCUGAGUGAAUGCUGGAUUUUAUUCUACAUGCCCAAUUCACUCCAAUAAGAUAAACUUGACUUCCUCCAGUGUGGCUUUCUUAUUUCAGCUUCUCUGACUGUGGCAUAAUUGAAAGUCAUAUUUCAUCUAGACCAUUGGUUUUCAACUCCAAAUGCAGGUGGCUUAUGAAGACUCAGCCUGAAUAUAUAAAGAGAACAGCAAACAAUCAUAGUUGCAUAUUAAAGACAAUCUAUUUCUCCGUAAAGGAAAGUAAAGUGAGUCAUAUUACAUACAAGCCACAAUACAGAACUGAUCUGAAAUACACUGCGGAAUGGCCUUUCAGUCUAUGCUGGACUCUAACAGGAAAAAGGCAGAAGGUGGUCAAUGGUGCAUUUAUUUAAACCCCUCAUUUCCUCCCUGACGAGAAGAAGGACAACAGUUCUUAUUUUUCAUAUUAUUUUUGAAAAGGCAGAAAGGUUAAUUAUAUAUUGACAUGAUUUGGAUCUGUGUCCUCACCAUAAUCUCAUGUCAAAUUGUAAUCCCCAGUGUUUGAGGUGGGGCCAGGUGGGAGGUGAUUGGAUCGUGGAGGUGGAUUUCUCAUGCAUGGUUUAGCACCAUCUUCUUGGUGCUAUUCUCGUGAUAGUGAGUAAGUUCUCACGAGAUCUGGUUGUUUAAAGGUGUGAAGAACCUCCCCUCUGUCUCUCUUGCUCCUGUUCCUGCCAUGUAAGAUAUGCUGGCUCCCCCUUUGCCUUCUGCCAUGAUUGUAAGUAUCCAGAGGCCUCUCCAGAAGCUGAGCAGAUGUCAGCACCAUGCUUCCUGUACAGCCUGUGGAACCAUGAGCCAAUUAAACCUCAUUCCUUUACAAAUUACCCAGUCUCGGGUUUUUCUUUAUAGCAAUGCAAGAACAGACUAAUAGAGGUAAUUUGUGAUGUUUCUUGAUGAAAGAAUCAGCUGAAACUCGAGAAUUAAUACAUUCAUUGAAGAUCAGACAAAUAUCAUAGAAACCGAGAAAGUAUCCAUCAUGGAACAAGAAAGUUCAGCUCAAAAAGCUGAUUUUUUCAAAGUACAAAAUGAAAUACCAUUUCAGGCAUGGAUCAUGACUCAAAGAAGCUCUUCACUUUGACCAGCACGGGGUUGAUUCAUUAACUCCAUUGUUCUCAAAUGAAUCCCACGGUGUCCCAAGAGAAACUCUGGAGAGGCUUCACCAAGAACAGUAAUUAUAGCUUUUCCAUGUUAUCUAGCAUUCAAUAAAUUCUUCCUAAUGUGA